GCCACCAAGUUGUUACAUGAAAUCUGCAGUUUCAUAAUUUCCGUGGGUCGGGCCGGGCGGGCCAGGCGCUGGGCACGGUGAUGGCCACCACUGGGGCCCUGGGCAACUACUACGUGGACUCGUUCCUGCUGGGCGCCGACGCCGCGGAUGAGCUGAGCGUUGGCCGCUAUGCGCCGGGGACCCUGGGCCAGCCUCCCCGGCAGGCGGCGACGCUGGCCGAGCACCCCGACUUCAGCCCGUGCAGCUUCCAGUCCAAGGCGACGGUGUUUGGCGCCUCGUGGAACCCAGUGCACGCGGCGGGCGCCAACGCUGUACCCGCUGCGGUGUACCACCACCAUCACCACCACCCCUACGUGCACCCCCAGGCGCCCGUGGCGGCGGCGGCGCCGGACGGCAGGUACAUGCGCUCCUGGCUGGAGCCCACGCCCGGUGCGCUCUCCUUCGCGGGCUUGCCCUCCAGCCGGCCUUAUGGCAUUAAACCUGAACCGCUGUCGGCCAGAAGGGGUGACUGUCCCACGCUUGACACUCACACUUUGUCCCUGACUGACUAUGCUUGUGGUUCUCCUCCAGUUGAUAGAGAAAAACAACCCAGCGAAGGCGCCUUCUCUGAAAACAAUGCUGAGAAUGAGAGCGGCGGAGACAAGCCCCCCAUCGAUCCCAAUAACCCAGCAGCCAACUGGCUUCAUGCGCGCUCCACUCGGAAAAAGCGGUGCCCCUAUACAAAACACCAGACCCUGGAACUGGAGAAAGAGUUUCUGUUCAACAUGUACCUCACCAGGGACCGCAGGUACGAGGUGGCUCGACUGCUCAACCUCACCGAGAGGCAGGUCAAGAUCUGGUUCCAGAACCGCAGGAUGAAAAUGAAGAAAAUCAACAAAGACCGAGCAAAAGACGAGUGAUGCCAUUUGGGCUUAUUUAGAAAAAAGGGUAAGCUAGAGAGAAAAAGAAAGAACUGUCCGUCCCCCUUCCGCCUUCUCCCUUCUCUCACCCCCACCCUAGCCUCCACCAUCCCCGCACAAAGCGGCUCUAAACCUCAGGCCACAUCUUUUCCAAGGCAAACCCUGUUCAGGCUGGCUCGUAGGCCUGCCGCUUUGAUGGAGGAGGUAUUGUAAGCUUUCCAUUUUCUAUAAGAAAAAGGAAAAGUUGAGGGGGGGGCAUUAGUGCUGAUAGCUGUGUGUGUUAGCUUGUAUAUAUAUUUUUAAAAAUCUACCUGUUCCUGACUUAAAACAAAAGGAAAGAAACUACCUUUUUAUAAUGCACAACUGUUGAUGGUAGGCUGUAUAGUUUUUAGUCUGUGUAGUUAAUUUAAUUUGCAGUUUGUGCGGCAGAUUGCUCUGCCAAGAUACUUGAACACUGUGUUUUAUUGUGGUAAUUAUGUUUUGUGAUUCAAACUUCUGUGUACUGGGUGAUGCACCCAUUGUGAUUGUGGAAGAUAGAAUUCAAUUUGAACUCAGGUUGUUUAUGAGGGGAAAAAAACAGUUGCAUAGAGUAUAGCUCUGUAGUGGAAUAUGUCUUCUGUAUAACUAGGCUGUUAACCUAUGAUUGUAAAGUAGCUGUAAGAAUUUCCCAGUGAAAUAAAAAAAAAUUUUAAGUGUUCUCGGGGAUGCAUAGAUUCAUCAUUUUCUCCACCUUAAAAAUGCGGGCAUUUAAGUCUGUCCAUUAUCUAUAUAGUCCUGUCUUGUCUAUUGUAUAUAUAAUCUAUAUGAUUAAAGAAAAUAUGCAUAAUCAGACAAGCUUGAAUAUUGUUUUUGCACCAGACGAACAGUGAGGAAAUUCGGAGCUAUACAUAUGUGCAGAAGGUUACUACCUAGGGUUUAUGCUUAAUUUUAAUUGGAGGAAAUGAAUGCUGAUUGUAACGGAGUUAAUUUUAUUGAUAAUAAAUUAUACACUAUGAAACCGCCAUUGGGCUACUGUAGAUUUGUAUCCUUGAUGAAUCUGGGGUUUCCAUCAGACUGAACUUACACUGUAUAUUUUGCAAUAGUUACCUCAAGGCCUACUGACCAAAUUGUUGUGUUGAGAUGAUAUUUAACUUUUUGCCAAAUAAAAUAUAUUGAUUCUUUUCUA